GCAGACUGAAGACGCCCUCCGUCAGCGACGCCGUCGCAAUGGCCAUUUGUCAAUUCUUCCUUCAAGGCCGGUGCCGCUUUGGAGAUCGGUGCUGGAACGAACAUCCCGGUGCUAGGGGUGCAGGAGGAGGACGGCAGCAACCGCAGCAGCAGCCUUCAGGUAAUAAUAGACGUGGAUGGAAUACAACUAGCCAGAGAUAUUCCAAUGUCAUCCAGCCAUCCAGUUUCUCCAAAUCCACACCAUGGGGGGGCAGCAGAGAUCAAGAAAAGCCAUAUUUCAGUUCUUUUGAUUCUGGAGCUUCAACUAACAGGAAGGAAGGCUUUGGAUUGUCUGAGAACCCAUUUGCUUCACUUAGUCCUGAUGAGCAGAAAGAUGAAAAGAAACUUCUGGAAGGAAUUGUAAAAGAUAUGGAGGUUUGGGAAUCAUCAGGGCAGUGGAUGUUUUCUGUUUAUUCACCAGUGAAAAAGAAACCUAAUAUUUCAGGUUUUACAGACAUUUCACCAGAGGAAUUGAGGCUUGAAUACCAUAACUUCUUAACCAGCAAUAACUUACAGAGUUAUCUAAAUUCUGUCCAACGUUUAAUAAAUCAAUGGAGGAACAGGGUAAAUGAACUGAAAAGUCUAAAUAUAUCAACUAAAGUAGCUUUGAAAUGCCUUUGGAAGAUAUAUACCCACCUGUCUCCAAAGAUCUAUGGUCCCGACUGUGGCAAGUUCAUUAUCUUUCUCUCUGAUGUAAAGGAUGGAGUAAAUCAAGCAGCACCUGCAUUUGGAUUUGGCAGCAGUCAAGCAGCAACAUUUAUGUCGCCAGGCUUUCCAGUCAAUAACAGCAGCAGUGAUAAUGCUCAGAACUUUAGUUUUAAAACAAACUCUGGAUUUGCUGCUGCCUCUUCUGGAAGCCCUGCUGGUUUUGGGAGUUCCCCAGCAUUUGGAGCUGCAGCCUCUACCAGUUCAGGUAUCUCUACUUCUGCUCCAGCUUUUGGAUUUGGGAAGCCUGAAGUCACAUCGGCUGCAUCAUUUUCAUUCAAAAGCCCUGCAGCUUCCAGUUUUGGAUCACCUGGAUUUUCAGGACUUCCAGCUUCCUUGGCAACAGGUCCUGUCAGAGCUCCAGUGGCCCCAGCCUUUGGAGGUGGCAGUUCUGUGGCUGGUUUUGGUAGUCCGGGCUCACAUUCUCACACUGCUUUUUCUAAGCCAUCCAGUGACACUUUUGGAAAUAGCAGCAUAUCCACUUCUCUGUCAGCCUCAAGCAGCAUCAUUGCAACAGAUAAUGUGUUAUUCACACCCAGAGAUAAACUAACAGUAGAAGAACUGGAACAAUUUCAAUCCAAGAAAUUUACUCUGGGAAAAAUUCCAUUAAAGCCUCCACCUCUGGAACUUCUAAAUGUUUAAAAGGGCAAUUUUAAAUACAAAAAAGAAUGAUGUUUAAAAUUGCUUUGAGUGAUUCAUACAGAGAUGUAUAUAUGCAUACAUGUAUAUAUUCAUAAGGAAUAUAAGCUUCCAUCAAUAGUGAUUUUAAAUUUGAUUUUUUUCUUAACUCUAAAUAUUUAAGUAAAAAGUAACAAAAACUCUGCAAGCAAGGGAAUUUUUUUGUACUGUAAUUUUGAAUGGAACUGAAAAAUUAUGCACGAAUAAAGUACUUUUCUCAUGCCA